AAGAAGAGGAGCACACCACACCAGAAACAGACAUCUUGCAGUGUUUCACUGUCUCAACCUUAUCUGCACAGUCCGAGGUCAGUCUGAGAGAGCUUCUGAGAGACCCAGGAUGAAGGGAUGCAGUGAGGUCAAGAGCCCAACCUUCUUUCACUGACACCCACCUCUAAGGACUCAGAGAGACAUGAAUAAAAUGGGCCUCAACAAUCCCAAGAGACCACUCAAGGACAAUGGGAGCCACUGGGCUUGGCUUUCUACUUUCCUGGAGACAAGACAAUUUGAAUGGCACUGACUGCCAGGGAUGCAAUAUUUUAUACUUCUCUGAGACUACGGGGAGCAUGUGUUCUGAACUUUCCUUGAACAGAGGUCUUGAGGCCAGAAGGAAGAAGGAUCUUAAAGACUCAUUUCUCUGGAGAUAUGGGAAGGUUGGCUGUAUCUCACUUCCACUUCGUGAGAUGACCGCCUGGAUUAACCCACCCCAAAUUUCAGAGAUUUUCCAAGGCUACCACCAGAGGGUGCACGGAGCUGAUGCACUGAGCCUGCAAACCAACUCUCUGAGAAGCAGGUUAUCUUCACAGUGCCUCGGACAGAGCUUCCUUCUCAGGACACUCGAGAGAGGCCGUGGUUUCAGGGCACUUGGGGACAUCUGUGGCCACGUUCAUGAAGAAGACUAAGCCUACUUCAUCUCAGGACCCGCCCAAGAGUGGCCGCGGCUUUGGGACACCUGGGGUCGGGUCCACCAUGAGGAUAAAACCUCCUUCUCUUCUGGACAUGUCCAGGAGUGGCCGUUGCUACAAGUCACCUGGUGCUACGACCAGGGUGAGAAUAAAGACGUCUCCUCAGGACCCUCCCAGGAGAGUACAUGGCAUUGAGACAUCUGGCGGCCAAGUGAGGAAAAGACACCCUGUCUGCAGCACCCAGAACUGAGGAGGGGCACUGCCCUGGGCCUUACUUCCCAGCCCUGGCCUCCAAUUCUGACCUUACAAAAGUGUCCCUUGAGUGAGGCAGUGACCACGCAUUGUCACAGCUACCAAAGUGUGGUUUGCAGAUGAUCUGGGCUUGUUUCUGGCAGAGAUUCUGGUACAGAGAAAGGAGAGGCGCUGAGUGGAACCACGAUGGGCUGAGGCCAGGGGAGACAUCGCAACCUCCAACAACACUUUUUUUCAUGCUUUAAUAACUCAUUUUUCUUAGAGAACUAAAGUAGUUGAAACAAUAUAGAAACAUUUUUUAAGUAGGCAUAU